CUCUCUCCGGCCUCACUUGCGGGAACACGUCCCUGGGGCCGGGGGCUCAGGGACAGGCAUGUGUUGCCCUAAACUGGGCAUCUGUGGACACGGCGUAGUUCACUCAGUCUUCCCCACAGUUCACCCCGUUUAAGGCAUUGAAGCAGAACUUGAAUGUGCAAGCCAAAGUCAGCAGGAGCCAGAGAGUGCAGGAUGUUGCUGUGAAUUUGGCCAAAACUGACUGGUCUGGCAUCAAAUAACUUGAGCCGCAUUCCCAGCCUUGGUGCCCUUGGCACUACAGGAGUAAUGCCAAAGCUGACUUGACGGACAGCCCGACUCUCUGCCCGCUGGAGGCAGGGCACAGGGCUUCCGUUUCCCGGGAGGGCUCAGGGAGGACUGGGGUCUCCGUGUCCAGUCAAGAUUUCUGGAAUUGACAACACUUGACGGCCAGUGUGUCCUCUUCUCCUUCUGGGUGACGUGGAGUGCUUGCAUGAGCUGAGAUAGGUGUCACUGUGGGGGAACCGAAUCACAGGGCACAAAGCUGGGUCCCCCCAAGAAGGGCUGGAGCUGGGCAAGAAGGGGUCUGCUGGUUCAGGGCUUGAGCUCCAGCCACGCUGCCCUCUAGGCUCCGCCUUUCCUAGCUGGCAUGAGGGACCCCUGGGAAAGGCCCCAGAAGAUCCUUCCCCCUGUGGAGUUGGGCGUGUUGGCGUGGGUAGGAGGCGAGGUCCCGGCCCCCACGUCCCCCCACAGGCACUCCAGUGCGAUGUCUCGGUGGAGGAGGACGACCGCCAGGAGUGGACGUUCACGCUCUAUGACUUUGACAACUGCGGGAAGGUCACCAGGGAGGACAUGUCCAGCCUCAUGCACACCAUCUAUGAGGUCGUGGAUGCCUCGGUCAACCACUCCUCGGGCAGCAGCAAGACCCUCCGUGUGAAGCUAACCGUCAGCCCUGAGCCCUCCAGCAAGAGGAAGGAGGGUCCUCCUGCUGGCCAGGACCGGGAGCCCACCCGUUGCAGGAUGGAGGGUGAACUGGCAGAGGAGCCAAGGGUGGCUGACAGGAGGUUGUCUGCACACGUCAGGCGUCCACUCUCCUUCCUGCUCUGCGAGGAGGUGGGUGCUGGUCAGGAUGCACCCCGGACCCCUGCCGCCUGCUGUAGGCACCCCGUCAUCAGGGGUGCGCCACCCAGUCUGUGCGGGGGUCAGGCCCUUCUCUGUGCUCCAAGCAGGAGGCCCAGUACUGACCCCCAGCCCUGCUCGGAGCGGGGGCCCUACUGCGUGGACGAGAACACGGAGCGCAGAAACCACUACCUGGACCUCGCCGGGAUUGAGAACUACACGUCCAGAUUCGGCCCUGGGUCCCCUCCUGUGCAAGCAAAGCAGGAGCCCCAGGGCAGGGCCUCGCACCUCCAGGCCCGGUCCCGCUCCCAGGAGCCAGAUACACAUGCCGUACACCACCGCAGGUCACAGGUGCUGGUGGAACACGUCGUGCCAGCCUCGGAGCCUGCUGCCCGGGCCCUGGACACGCAGCCCCGGCCGAAGGGGCCGGAGAAGCAGUUCCUCAAGUCCCCCAAGGGCUCCGGGAAGCCGCCUGGGGUGCCAGCCAGCAGCAAGUCCGGGAAAGCCUUCAGCUACUACCUGCCGGCCGUCCUGCCGCCCCAGGCCCCUCAGGACGGCCACCACCUCCCGCAGCCCCCACCGCCACCCUACGGCCACAAGCGGUACCGCCAAAAGGGCAGGGAGGGCCACUCGCCACUCAAGGCCCCACACGCUCAGCCUGCCACAGUGGAGCACGAGGUGGUGCGGGACCUGCCGCCCACGCCAGCAGGAGAGGGCUACGCGGUGCCAGUGAUCCAGCGGCACGAGCACCACCACCACCACGAGCACCACCACCACCACCACCACCACCACUUCCACCCGUCCUAGCGCCACUGCCAAGCACACCUCGCUCCCAGCACACCACAGCCCGCGACCUCAGGGCAGGGAGCAGAGCAGCUGCCGGCUGUGUGCCCAUGGGGAGCCCAGCCCCCACCCCCCACCUCCGACAGCAAACAGCAACUGACUGCAGGUGCUGGCAUGAUGGAGGUGGUGCACCUUGGACACGUGGACAAGGCCCAGGCGCCCUCUGCUCUUCUGCCCUCGAUGCCACAUGGCGGUGAACACAUCUGAAGCCACUAUGUUUCCUGGCUCUAAGGCUCGUCUGUGUAACCCAUAAAACCUGCUUUGAUUCCAAAAUGAGGCCCUGGAGUGCGCAAGGAGUGCCCGGAUGCUUGGGGUGGGUGUUCCUCCCGGGGCUUCAAGGGGUGACUGCUGUAGGCUGUCCCAGUGCGAGGCCGGGAGCGAAUGGAAAAGCUGAGGCUUUGCCUGGCUUGUGCAUCAUGAAGUGAGAGGGGACAGGGCCGGUGGGGGGAAGCAGCUUGUGCUUAGCAGGGAGCAUCCGCGGCUCCCCGCAGGAGGCCAAGCAGCAGAAGGCAGCAGUGCUAGAAAGAGAAGUGC